GUGUGUUUGCCAAGCCAGGGCUGGAGCUUCCUGGACCCGCCUACCCUGGAGGGGAUGGAGCAGUGAAGGGCACCGGGCCAAGCGCUAGGCAUCUGGGGCUAAGGAGACAGAAGCCCGCGGUGCCCGUCCAUGCGGGCCCUCUGCCCCAGCACCCACAUCUCAGGACACCCCUUCCUCCCAGGAAGAAGACCCCCAAGAGCAAAGGGGCCAGCACCCCCGCUGCCUCCACGCUGCCCACCGCCAACGGGGCCCGACCGGCGCGCUCCGGGACUGCGCUUUCCGGCCCCGACGCGCCGCCCAACGGGCCCUUGCAGCCCGGCCGGCCCUCGCUUGGCGGCGGUGUCGACUUCUACGACGUCGCCUUCAAGGUCAUGCUGGUGGGGGACUCGGGUGUGGGGAAGACCUGUCUGCUGGUGCGAUUCAAGGAUGGUGCUUUCCUGGCGGGGACCUUCAUCUCCACCGUAGGCAUUGACUUCCGGAACAAAGUUCUGGACGUGGAUGGUGUGAAGGUGAAGCUGCAGAUGUGGGACACAGCUGGUCAGGAGCGGUUCCGCAGUGUUACCCAUGCCUACUACCGGGAUGCUCAUGCUCUGCUGCUGCUCUACGAUGUCACCAACAAGGCCUCCUUUGACAACAUCCAGGCCUGGCUGACCGAGAUCCACGAGUACGCCCAGCACGACGUGGCGCUCAUGCUGCUGGGGAACAAGGUGGACUCUGCCCAUGAGCGUGUGGUGAAGAGGGAGGACGGGGAGAAGCUGGCCAAGGAGUAUGGACUGCCCUUCAUGGAGACCAGCGCCAAGACGGGCCUCAACGUGGACUUGGCCUUCACAGCCAUAGCAAAGGAGUUGAAGCAGCGCUCCAUGAAGGCUCCCAGCGAGCCGCGCUUCCGGCUGCAUGAUUACGUUAAGAGGGAGGGUCGAGGGGCCUCCUGCUGCCGCCCUUGAACCUGGCUGAGCUCAGUCCUCUGGAGGAAGCCGUCCAGUCCCUAGAAGGCUGGACAGAGGGUCUCCAGGCCCUUCUGACUUUGUUGCCCAGUGGCCAACGCCCGAGUGUCUGUUUUCAGGAGCCCCAGGUCAAGCCUUGUCCCUUCCUCCUCCCAGCAACAGUCCCAACAAGCAGGCUUCUGAGAGCCCGUGGCCGCACACUGGCCGCCACGGAAAAGCAGUCUUCUGCACGGGACGGGGAGCGGCAAGUGGACAGACUUUGCCACGGUGCUCUGCUGCCCCCUCCUGGGCACGUCCAGGUGAGGGAGGGCUGGGGCUGGCACCACGCACAGUGCCUAACCCUAGAAAAGCCAUGUCUUCAGCCGCACAUGCUCAGGCAGCUAAGGGAGGACGCCUGCCCACGCCUGGGACAGAAGGCUUCACUGCUAAUCACAUCGUGCAUCUGUGUGUCCUGGGAGCUGCCUGCUCCCGGCCCACCCUCUAGGAGGCUCUGGCUCAAACAGCAAUAGGGUCUUCCUCACUGACCUUGGAGGAUGCCUGUGGCCUUGUGAUAAAAUGUGGGAAAUCACAGAAAACACCAGAAACAACAACUGCCAGCCCGGCCUGGCCACAGGUGAGGUCUGUGAUUUCCGAGCACGCUCCACCUUGCACUCAACUUGGCCUUUUGAUUGCACAAGCCUUUGUUUUCAGUCCUAGUGAAUAAAGUUGUGUUUUCUGGAGCGUCUGUCUCAUCUGUUGAAAAAA